AGUGCGUGUGGUGAGGCAGGACAUGGCGGAGGCAGGAAAAGUGCCCUUGAGCCUCGGGCUUACCGGAGGAGAAGCGGCAGAGUGGCCUCUGCAGCGGUACGCCCGCUGCAUACCCUCAAACACCAGAGACCCACCUGGGCCAUGCCUGGAAGCUGGGACAGCCCCCUGCCCCACAUGGAAGGUUUUUGAUUCCAAUGAAGAAUCUGGAUAUCUUGUUCUCACCAUAGUUAUAUCAGGUCAUUUCUUCAUUUUCCAAGGACAGACACUACUGGAAGGGUUUUCACUCAUUGGUAGCAAGGACUGGUUGAAGAUUGUAAGACGCGUGGAUUGUCUGUUGUUUGGAACAACGAUAAAGGACAAGAGUCGCCUGUUUCGAGUACAGUUCAGUGGAGAGUCAAAGGAGCAGGCGCUGGAACACUGCUGCAGUUGUGUUCAGAAGCUGGCACAAUACAUAACCGUGCAGGUGCCUGAUGGAAACAUCCAGGAGCUUCAGCUGAUUCCUGGCCCACCCAGGGCAACUGAAAGUCAAGGGAAGGAUUCUGCAAAGAGUGUCCCACGGCAGCCUGGAUCCCACCAGCACUCAGAACAACAGCAAGUGUGUGUAACAGCGGGCACAGGCGCUCCAGACGGAAGGACCUCACUGACGCAGUUAGCUCAGACUCUUCUGGCAUCGGAGGAGCUGCCCCAUGUCUAUGAACAAUCUGCAUGGGGUGCAGAAGAGUUAGGCCCCUUCCUACGUUUGUGCCUUAUGGAUCAGAAUUUCCCAGCAUUUGUGGAAGAGGUAGAAAAGGAACUGAAAAAGCUGGCGGGUUUGAGAAAUUAAUGCUCUAUAUACAUAUAUAACUAAGGAACUUCAAAGUAUUGAAAAAUGCUUCCUCCUAAAAUUAAAGAAGAUAUUAGAAUAAAGAGUAUUAUCCAAA